GGGAUGGCAGCCCUAAACACAGCAUGGCAACUCAUCUACUCACUCAUGAAAGAUUAAAAAAUGGAAACCAACGUAUUUCAUCUUAUGCUCUGCGUCACUUCUGCUCGGACUCAUAAAUCCACGUCUCUUUGCUUUGGCCACUUCAACUCAUAUCCAAGCCUUCCUUUAAUUCAUGAUUUAUUGCUAGGAUGAUGUCAGGUCAUAGGAUGAUAUAUAUAAUCAGUGAGCAGGCAGAAUGAGGAGACAGUUGAAAGUUCUCUACAACAGAAGCCAAGAAGGAAGCCGUCUAUCUUGUGGCGAUCAUGUAUAAGCUGGCCUCCUGCUGUUUGCUUUUCAUAGGAUUCUUAAAUCCUCUCUUAUCUCUUCCUCUCCUUGACUCCAGGGAAAUAUCCUUUCAACUCUCAGCACCUCAUGAAGACGCGCGCUUAACUCCGGAGGAGCUAGAAAGAGCUUCCCUUCUACAGAUACUGCCAGAGAUGCUGGGUGCAGAAAGAGGGGAUAUUCUCAGGAAAGCAGACUCAAGUACCAACAUUUUUAACCCAAGAGGAAAUUUGAGAAAGUUUCAGGAUUUCUCUGGACAAGAUCCUAACAUUUUACUGAGUCAUCUUUUGGCCAGAAUCUGGAAACCAUACAAGAAACGUGAGACUCCUGAUUGCUUCUGGAAAUACUGUGUCUGAAGUGAAAUAAGCAUCUGUUAGUCAGCUCAGAAACACCCAUCUUAGAAUAUGAAAAAUAACACAAUGCUUGAUUUGAAAACAGUGUGGAGAAAAACUAGGCAAACUACACCCUGUUCAUUGUUACCUGGAAAAUAAAUCCUCUAUGUUUUGCACA